GUCAGACAAUUCUUAGAUUCUCGAUCUUUUUUUCCCUGUAGACUCAUUAAUACCAUCUGCCAAGAAGUUACUCCAGAAGUUACUCCCGAAGCUCUCAUGACUGAACAAGGGAAGAAUAGAGUUAGUGUGUAAGACUGGAAAUAGAAUUUGUCCCAUAGCACCAGAAUCUAUUUUCUCUAGAAUGGUAUGAAAGCAUUUCCAGUAUUUUUUUAUCAGUAAUAUCAAAAUAAUUUUCAAUGAAGUAUCAAAUCUAGAUGGUAAGGACUGUAUUUAGAAGUAGUUUUUUAUAAUCAUUUAUAUACUACAAGAGAAUUCAAUUGCCUCAAGUGAAUUUGAAAUUUAGGAAGAAAAAAAUAUAUACCAUAUUAUUAACAAGGACGUUUUCUUAGGGGAAAAAUCUUAGAUAGCAUCAAACUGGAGCCAAAGACAUAUUUGCCUAUGUCAGGCACCUAUAAAAUAUGCUUACUAUAAAAUAUGCUUAAGAUGCUAUUUAACAUAUAGACAGGGUUCAACAACUAGUGGCUGCUGUUUUAAUAAUAAGCAUAACUAAAUUAUUAGUGUCCUCCAACUUCUAUGCUUCAUUUCAAGCUAUACCACCUGUCAAUGCCACUUGCCCAGAAAGUCUGAUCUCAUCAUCCCAAAGAGAAACCCACUGUUAUUCGCUUCUCCAUAAAAAUCCAUAUUUUUUUUUCAGUUUUCAUGUUUCUUAGAGUUUAAUGCUUAAAUAGUAUGGGAUUUUACACAAGUGACCUGGCAUUUAGAUGGAGAGCAUUUUUAAUUUCUACAACAACAGUAACAAAGGGGAGAAGGUCGGCAGUGAGAGAAGGGGAAAGAAAGGGGAAGAACGAGGGAAUGAACACCUGGAAGACAGGUUGAGCCAGGUGAGAACAGUCUCCACCUGUCAGUCAGCAGCGUCUUCCCAGCUGCUCUGCCAGUGAGGCUCUGUCUGUCUGGAAUACACAUCUGUUGGUCUUCCCUGUGGGAUUGGAGUGUUCCUUUCCUGCAUCCAAAAUCUUUGCUUAGGAGCACUCCUCCCAGCUCUUGGUUGAAGAACAAUCACUGGCUAGGGCCAGUGAUAAGAAAAAGAUAUCCUUUAAUCAGGAAUGGGUUUUGUUGUGGUUCUUAAUAAAUGUGUUCAUAUUUUAAAAGGCAAUCAGUAGUUGUAAAUGAUGGGAUAAACCCACGACUCUCAACUCCAGCUCUACACGGCAGCUUUCUCACGGAGCAGAUCGCCUUAUAAGUACAGAAAAUGAACUUUGUGCCCAGGAUGCUCUAUGAAAACUUCCUCUGGUUCUAUGUAUGGUGCUAAUUCAGAAUAUCCCAUUGGCUGUGGGGCUUCAAAGAGACUGUUCACUUUCCUGUGUAUGUGAGCGUGUGUAAUUUCUGUUUACAUUACAGAAGGCUUUAAAGUUAAAAUUUAUCUUUGGGAAAUCUUACUUUCAUUUUACAAAAAUCCUUCCUUUUUGGAAGCCUCCUUACAUGAAAGUAAACAAAUUUCAAUACAAGUUUCUGUGUGUGCAACACAUGUCUUUAACCUUCCUGGAACCGGUGACCUGCAACUCCCAACAUUCUCAUCCAGUUGAAAGUCACAUUUACUAUGAAACUUAAUCUUUAAGGCUAUACUCCCUGUGCCUAAUUCUUUGUCACUCCUCCUCUCCACGUGGUCCUUUUUUGGGGUUAUUCAUGUGAGGCAAACAUUGGCUAGAAUUUACUUUGAUUUGCAAUACUUUGAGGCACACUAAUUUCAGUUAAAACUGGAAAAGAAACUAGUACUAGAGUCCUGUAAAUAGAUUUCAUUAUAAACAUAUACUACUCAUGAAAAUACAAUGCCUGGAGCAUGACAGUUACCCCAUAAAUACUUGAAUGUUCAUGAACAAUCGAGUGGGAAAAAAAUUAAAAUUCUCCCAGUGGUAAGUCUGUCUUCAGUCCAUAGUCGUAUAGGUACAGUCAUUGUAUCACUUCCAUUAUUGCCUGUAUGUAUUGCUAGCUUGAACAUUUUUAUUAAAAUGGCCCCUCAGAGCCAGGUGCAGUGGCUCUUGCCUGUAAUCUCAGCACUUUGGGAGGCCAAGGUGAGCAGAUCACCUGAGCUUAAGAGUUUGAGACCAGCCUAGGCAACAGAGUGAAAUCCUGUCUGUCUCUACAAAAAAAUUUCAAAAACUAGCCUGGCAUGGUGGUGCGUGCCUGUAGUCCCAGCUACUCAGGAGGCUGAGGUGUGAGGAUGGCUCGAGUCUGGGAGGCGGAGGUUGCAGUGAGCCAAGAUCAUGCUACCGCAUUCCAGCCUGGGUAAGAGAGCCAGACCUAGGGGGAAAAAAAAAAUCAUGUUUAGGCCUAGGACUUAAAGGAAAAAAAUGGCCCCUGGGGCUAAAUGUAGCCAACUUCCUUGAAAAAUCAAACAAACCGAAGAUUUAACAAUUGAAGUGACCAUUUUCUCACACCGAAUUUAGACAAUUCCUCCAAAAGGGCCAAAUGUUUGUAUAUAAGUACAACCUGAGUUUUCUAUUAUAGUUUUUAUCAUGUGGGAGUUAUCACAGGGACUUCAUUUUUCUGCCUUAAAAAUGCUGGCAGGAAAAAAAAUUAGUCAAUUGGGCAGAUAUAUUAGAAAGUGGCUUAGUGUCUUAGAAAUAAAAUCCAAAAACAUGUGUGCUGCACAGAUGUAUGAGGGUCCCUUUCCCUCCGGGUUCUAGGAGUUGUCUGUAGCCCGUUCACAGAGUAGUAGCAGCCUUGACCCUCUCUCGUUUGCCCACCCUCUUCCAAUAGCUAGUGAUUUCAGCAACUACCAAUUUCGGUAUUUCUGCAGGCUCUUCUGAGAAUGCUCAAAAACGACAGAAUGGCUUUUCAGGCAACCUCCAGAGACUAUCUCAGAGAAGAGAGCCUAACUCUGUGCUUGGGCACAUGUGGGCUAUUUUCCAAGGAACCUCAUACACUCCCUGAAGCCCGCAGAUUUCAGAACUGGGUUCAGUAUACUUCACAAUGAAGGAUGGGUAUUGAGUGUUUGUGCUCUUACCUGAAAAUGGCUGCGAUGAGUCAGAUAAGACAAGAGGUGUCACCAUCAGUACCUGGAUAUUAACUUCUCUUUUCUUUCCUAGGGAAUGCAGUCGGAUUUUUGGUGAAGAUGGUCUGACGCUGAAACUCUUUCUUAAAAGAACUGCUCCCUUUUCUAUUCUAUGGACUUUGACUAAUUACCUUUAUUUACUGGCUUUAAAGAAGCUGACGGCCACGGAUGUCUCCGCUCUGUUCUGUUGUAACAAAGCCUUUGUCUUCUUGCUGUCAUGGAUUGUGCUGAAAGACAGGUUCAUGGGAGUGAGGUUGCUGCAAUAAUGGCAAUUACCGGCAUUGUCAUGAUGGCAUAUGCAGAUAAUUUCCACGCUGAUUCCAUCAUAGGAGUGGCAUUUGCGGUGGGCUCAGCCUCUACAUCUGCAUUAUAUAAGGUCUUGUUUAAAAUGUUUCUUGGAAGUGCCAACUUUGGGGAAGCUGCACACUUUGUCUCCACCUUGGGUUUCUUCAAUUUGAUCUUCAUCUCCUUCACCCCAGUCAUCUUGUAUUUCACCAAGGUGGAGCACUGGUCCUCUUUUGCUGCUCUGCCAUGGGGCUGUCUCUGUGGGAUGGCAGGGCUGUGGCUGGCCUUCAACAUCCUGGUGAAUGUUGGGGUGGUGCUGACAUACCCAAUCCUAAUCUCCAUUGGGACAGUGCUCAGCGUUCCUGGAAAUGCAGCUGUGGAUCUCCUAAAGCAGGAGGUGAUAUUCAAUGUUGUCCGCCUGGCUGCUACCAUCAUCAUCUGCAUUGGGUUUCUGCUGAUGCUGUUGCCUGAGGAAUGGGAUGAAAUCACCCUGAGGUUCAUCAACAGCCUGAAGGAAAAGAAGAGUGAGGAGCAUGUGGAUGAUGUGACUGAUCCCAGCAUACACCUGCGGGGCAGAGGCAGAGCCAAUGGGACAGUGUCUAUACCACUGGCUUAGAGAGGGACAUAUUUUGAAUGCACGUGUAUGUAUAUUCUGUGAAUAUAACAAAAUUUUCUCACUACCUGUACACUCAAACGACAGUAUUAACUCUGAAUUUGGAUAAAUCAUAUGUGAAAUAAUGCCAACAAUAAAAGUUUACAUUUAUAUGCUUAUCAAGGAAUUGGUGUAAAUAAUCAUAAUGGAUUUUUUUAUUAAAACACAUUUGUCCUUGU